GAGAAAGUUGUCUGCGUCUCGAGGCGAGUUGGCGGAGCUGUGCGCGCGGCGGGGCGAUGGGGGGCUCGGGCAGUCGCCUGUCCAAGGAGCUGCUGGCCGAGUACCAGGACUUGACGUUCCUGACGAAGCAGGAGAUCCUCCUUUCUGUGUACGUGGUUUUAGCUCCUCACCUGGUUGACAAUGAGCAGCAGGCAAGGAGUGGGAAUGAACACACAGGGAGACCGAUCGCUGAGAACACCGACAGUUCCCCUCUCUCUACCAGAGCCCACAGGCGGUUUUGUGAGCUGCUUCCCCAGGAGCAGCGGAGCGUGGAGUCGUCACUUCGGGCACAAGUGCCCUUCGAGCAGAUUCUCAGCCUUCCAGAGCUCAAGGCCAACCCCUUCAAGGAGCGAAUCUGCAGGGUCUUCUCCACAUCCCCAGCCAAAGACAGCCUUAGCUUUGAGGACUUCCUGGAUCUCCUCAGUGUGUUCAGUGACACAGCCACGCCAGACAUCAAGUCCCAUUAUGCCUUCCGCAUCUUUGACUUUGAUGAUGACGGAACCUUGAACAGAGAAGACCUGAGCCGGCUGGUGAACUGCCUCACGGGAGAGGGCGAGGACACACGGCUUAGUGCGUCUGAGAUGAAGCAGCUCAUCGACAACAUCCUGGAGGAGUCUGACAUUGACAGGGAUGGAACCAUCAACCUCUCUGAGUUCCAGCACGUCAUCUCCCGUUCUCCAGACUUUGCCAGCUCCUUUAAGAUUGUCCUGUGACAGCAGCCCCAGCGUGUGUCCUGGCACCCUGUCCAAGAACCUUUCUACUGCUGAGCUGUGGCCAAGGUCAAGCCUGUGUUGCCAGUGCGGGCCAAGCUGGCCCAGCCUGGAGCUGGCGCUGUGCAGCCUCACCCCGGGCAGGGGCGGCCCUCGUUGUCAGGGCCUCUCCUCACUGCUGUUGUCAUUGCUCCGUUUGUGUUUGUACUAAUCAGUAAUAAAGGUUUAGAAGUUUGACCCUAUGUGUGACAUGAGAUACACUGGUAUGAGGAAGGACUGGACUUCUCUUCUAAGAGCCUUCAAUCAUCCUAGGAAUAAGCAGCAUAUCGAGCAGAGGCCAGCGGGAAGUCAAGCCGCACCCACGCUGGCUGUCCCCGUGGGAGGGUGUGAGGAUGAAGGGGCAGCAGGAGGUGUGGGACUCGCCUGUAUCCUGAUUGGGGUGGUGGUUAGAUGAGUCUCUGCAUGCAUCAAAAUGUAAAGAACCGUACAUCAGUAAAGUCUAUUUUACUGCA